AGUGCUGAAGUAGGCGCGGACGUGCCCGGUGCCUGGCGCGUGGUAGCAGGCGCCCGGUGCCCCGGCCGGCGAAGACCAUGGCGUUCAUGGUGAAGACCAUGGUGGGCGGCCAGCUGAAGAACCUCACUGGGAGCCUGGGAGGCGGCGAGGAUAAGGGAGAUGGGGACAAGUCGGCAGCCGAAGCUCAGGGCAUGAGCCGGGAGGAGUACGAGGAGUAUCAGAAGCAACUCGUGGAAGAGAAGAUGGAGCGGGAUGCACAGUUCACACAGAGGAAGGCAGAGCGGGCCACACUGCGGAGCCACUUCCGAGACAAAUACCGGCUACCCAAGAACGAGACAGAUGAGAGCCAGAUCCAGAUGGCAGGUGGAGACGUGGAGCUGCCCCGGGAGCUGGCCAAGAUGAUCGAGGAGGACACAGAGGAGGAGGAGGAGAAGGCCUCAGUCCUUGGGCAGCUGGCCAGCCUUCCUGGCUUGAACCUGGGCUCACUCAAGGACAAGGCCCAGGCCACACUGGGGGAUCUCAAGCAAUCAGCUGAGAAGUGUCACGUCAUGUGACCACUUCCCCGGGGUUACCCACUGGGCUGGGCCCCCAUGAGGGCUAAGAGUGUGUCAACUUCCAGGGACCCAUACUCCAUUUGGGGCUUUGUUUCCCUUGCCCCAUCCUAGUUCCAAGACCUUUCCCAUCCAUGCCCCAAGCCUAUCUUCUGGUUUCUUCCUCUCCGCUGGGAGUAAAGUCCCCAUCUUCACUCUACCCUUCAGGACCCUCCCCACCAGCUCAGCCUGUGGAGGCCUCCCAAGAUUGUAGGAAUAGGCCCAUCCCUCUCUGGCCAUGGCCCCAAGUUCCUGCACACAGGAGCACCCACAGAGAGACACACACAGGACACAAAACCCCUGGCACGUUCAGAGACAGAAGCCACAGAUACAUCCCGGCACAGACAGACACACACGAGGCCAGCUCCCUUGCGUGUCCAGCCCCUCCAGACACCACCACUCAGAAACUCUGAGAGAGAGCAUGGGCAGACACCCUCAGCAGACAGGAGGCCUGAGUUCCAGUCUCCACCUUUAUUGUUCUUGAAAGCCCCUGCUCUCUCUGAGCCUUAUUUCAUCAUCUGUAAAAUGGGAAUGUCCUGAAUGACUUCUAAGGCUCUUUCUGGCUUGAACUGUCAGAGCCAAGCCCACAUCCCUCCUUGGGCAGGGCAGCAGCUGCUGCCACAGCCUCCAGCGGCUGCCACUGUGGGCUCUGGGAGCCGGAGCGAUGCUGUGUGAGAGGCAGAGUGCCAAGGAUGAAGCUGGCACUGAACAGUAAGCGGCUCCAGGCCUCCUCUGGGCCCAGGGCCCAGCCAAUUUCUGUUCUGUUCCUGUAGAACGCUCUCUGGAUUCCAUAGCUGGAAUCUCCUCUCUUAGCUCAGUGAAAAAUAAAAAUCCCAAAUGGUGUGCCUACCUUCCCACUUCUUACUGGCUUCCAGGAGUCUUGGAGUUCAUAGCCCCCCGAGCCUGCCUUAAAGGGGUGUCCUCCACCCCCCACCUACAGCUUCACAGGAGGGGAGAAGGCAUCCAGUGCUAGGAGUAGAAGUGUCUCCAGCUCUGUUCUCUUGGGGCCCUGGGUGAAGGUGGGGUCUGGGGCUUAUGAAAUAGGUCUGGGCUUUGAGGAGGAUGGAGCAGCCUCAUUAUGUGGGGAAGAUGGGGCCUCUGGGGCGUCACUGAGACCACAGGUGGGGCCGGGGCUGGACCGCAGCUGUCUUGGGUGCCUGUGCCUACACCCCUCCUCACCCUAGAGACGGAAGAUGUGCAAAAAGAAAGAAGGAAGGGCAACUGCAUUCCAGCCCCACACUGUGAUGACUUUGAGCCUGUCCUUUCCCUCCUUGAGCCUGUCUUGCUUGUCCCCUGUAAAAUGAACAGUCCCCCUCUCCCCCAAAUAGUAAUAAUACAUGUUUCAAAGGGUGACCAUUUAUAAAGCAUAUGACAAACCAUAUCAAUAAAUGUAACUCAUUCUUUUAAAAAAA